GAGACCGGCAGCCUCUGUGCCAGGAGACACAGGUCUUGGAGGGAGCAGAGGAGGUGGCUGUGUCUCUGGAGGGACCCCUCCUCCUGGAGGACCCCAGGCAGCUCAUGGACCUUUCCAGACCCAGAUGGAGCCUGUGGAGGAGGGUCUUCCUCAUGGCCAGUCUGCUGGCCUGUGGGAUCUGCCAGGCCUCUGGCCAAAUCUUCAUCACCCAAACCCUGGGGAUCAAGGGAUAUCGGACUGUCGUGGCCCUGGAUAAGGUCCCUGAGGAUGUUCAGGAAUACAGCUGGUACUGGGGUGCAAACGACAGCGCAGGAAACAUGAUUAUCAGCCACAAACCGCCCAGUGCCCAGCAGCCUGGGCCCAUGUACACUGGCAGGGAGAGAGUGAACAGAGAAGGCAGCCUGUUGAUCAGGCCGACUGCAUUAAAUGACACGGGAAACUACACUGUUCGGGUGGUUGCAGGCAAUGAGACCCAAAGAGCAACCGGCUGGCUGGAGGUUCUAGAGUUGGGAAGCAAUCUGGGCAUCUCCGUCAAUGCCAGCUCCCUGGUGGAGAACAUGGAUUCUGUGGCUGCUGACUGCCUCACAAAUGUCACCAACAUCACGUGGUAUGUGAAUGAUGUGCCUACCUCUAGUAGUGACCGGAUGACAAUUUCCCCAGACGGCAAGACCCUCGUCAUCCUCAGGGUCAGCCGCUAUGACAGAACAAUUCAGUGCAUGAUAGAGAGUUUCCCAGAGAUCUUUCAGAGAAGUGAACGCAUCUCUCUGACUGUGGCCUAUGGGCCCGACUAUGUGCUGCUGAGGAGCAAUCCUGAUGAUUUCAACGGCAUUGUGACAGCUGAGAUCGGCUCCCAAGUGGAAAUGGAGUGUAUCUGCUAUUCCUUCCUGGAUCUCAAGUACCACUGGAUCCACAAUGGCUCCCUCCUGAACUUCUCAGAUGCAAAGAUGAACCUCUCGAGUCUUGCCUGGGAGCAGAUGGGCCGUUACCGAUGCACUGUGGAGAACCCCGUGACACAGCUGAUCAUGUACAUGGACGUCAGGAUCCAGGCCCCCCAUGAGGAUCUUACCUGUUGUCCACAGAGAUUUCUCCAUCUCAGGAUCCAUGGUGAUGUUCCUCAUCAUGCUGACAGUGCUGGGUGGCGUUUACAUCUGUGGAGUCCUGAUCCAUGCUCUGAUCAACCACUACUCAAUCAGGACAAAUCGGGCUCCAUGAGUGUCCACCCCAGACCUGAGGACAAGACCAGAAGGGCAAGCAGGUGAGGAGAGGGUGAUGGAGAAGGGCUGGGGGUCCCCAUAGGGCCAGCGAGGCUGAAAAGGGUCCAGGGUCUCUUUGGAGGGUACUGGCAAGAGAGGGACCCAGCCCAGUCACACGGAAGCCUGGAGAUGGAGGCUCCAGUAGGAGGUCUGCAGACCCCACCCGGGACCUGAAGAUGAUGUCGUGGGUAGCGUGGCCAUUGGGCGCUUCAUCUGCCAAUCAGAGCUGGUCAAUGGGUUGCAGGUCGGGGCGGGCCAUGCGCAAAGCUGGGCUCUAAUUCCAAGCGCCUCCUCCCUCAGCUCCGGCGCUUCCAGCUUCUCAGAUUUCUUCACCCAUGGAAUCAACAGCGAUGCUGUAAACUUAUGGCCAAGGGGUGCCAAUCAGUGGUUGUUCCACUCAGUGCCGAAUGAGAGAAGAGACCUUAGAAUCAGGCAGGGAUUAAAUUUCAGUCCUGCCCUGAGUACCGGAGCGACCUGAACGCAGCCCCAGUGAGGCUCCCUCACCUGGAUGCACCGUGGAACCAUCGUCAGCAUGAUUAGCACAUCCGUCAGCUCAAAUAUUUAAUUUUUUUUUUUUUUUGGUGACAACAUUUAAACUCCUCUCUUUUAGCCAUUUUGAAAUAUUCAAUACAUUAUUCUGUUAUUUGGAACAACA